GCAACCCACACCGCCCCUGCCAGCCACCAUGGGGCUGCCACUAGCCCGCCUGGCGGCUGUGUGCCUGGCCCUGUCUUUGGCAGGGGGCUCGGAGCUCCAGACAGAGGGCAGAACCCGAAACCACGGCCACAACGUCUGCAGCACCUGGGGCAACUUCCACUACAAGACCUUCGACGGGGACGUCUUCCGCUUCCCCGGCCUCUGCGACUACAACUUCGCCUCCGACUGCCGAGGCUCCUACAAGGAAUUUGCUGUGCACCUGAAGCGGGGUCCGGGCCAGGCUGAGGCCCCCGCCGGGGUGGAGUCCAUCCUGCUGACCAUCAAGGAUGACACCAUCUACCUCACCCGCCACCUGGCUGUGCUUAACGGGGCCGUGGUCAGCACCCCGCACUACAGCCCCGGGCUGCUCAUUGAGAAGAGCGAUGCCUACACCAAAGUCUACUCCCGCGCCGGCCUCACCCUCAUGUGGAACCGGGAGGAUGCACUCAUGCUGGAGCUGGACACUAAGUUCCGGAACCACACCUGUGGCCUCUGCGGGGACUACAACGGCCUGCAGAGCUAUUCAGAAUUCCUCUCUGACGGCGUGCUCUUCAGUCCCCUGGAGUUUGGGAACAUGCAGAAGAUCAACCAGCCCGAUGUGGUGUGUGAGGAUCCCGAGGAGGAGGUGGCCCCCGCAUCCUGCUCCGAGCACCGCGCCGAGUGUGAGAGGCUGCUGACCGCCGAGGCCUUCGCGGACUGUCAGGACCUGGUGCCGCUGGAGCCGUAUCUGCGCGCCUGCCAGCAGGACCGCUGCCGGUGCCCGGGCGGUGACACCUGCGUCUGCAGCACCGUGGCCGAGUUCUCCCGCCAGUGCUCCCACGCCGGCGGCCGGCCCGGGAACUGGAGGACCGCCACGCUCUGCCCCAAGACCUGCCCCGGGAACCUGGUGUACCUGGAGAGCGGCUCGCCCUGCAUGGACACCUGCUCACACCUGGAGGUGAGCAGCCUGUGCGAGGAGCACCGCAUGGACGGCUGUUUCUGCCCAGAAGGCACCGUAUAUGACGACAUCGGGGACAGUGGCUGCGUUCCUGUGAGCCAGUGCCACUGCAGGCUGCACGGACACCUGUACACACCGGGCCAGGAGAUCACCAAUGACUGCGAGCAGUGUGUCUGUAACGCUGGCCGCUGGGUGUGCAAAGACCUGCCCUGCCCCGGCACCUGUGCCCUGGAAGGCGGCUCCCACAUCACCACCUUCGAUGGGAAGACGUACACCUUCCACGGGGACUGCUACUAUGUCCUGGCCAAGGGUGACCACAACGAUUCCUACGCUCUCCUGGGCGAGCUGGCCCCCUGUGGCUCCACAGACAAGCAGACCUGCCUGAAGACGGUGGUGCUGCUGGCUGACAAGAAGAAGAAUGUGGUGGUCUUCAAGUCCGAUGGCAGUGUACUGCUCAACGAGCUGCAGGUGAACCUGCCCCACGUGACCGCGAGCUUCUCUGUCUUCCGCCCGUCUUCCUACCACAUCAUGGUGAGCAUGGCCAUUGGCGUCCGGCUGCAGGUGCAGCUGGCCCCAGUCAUGCAACUCUUUGUGACACUGGACCAGGCCUCCCAGGGGCAGGUGCAGGGCCUCUGCGGGAACUUCAACGGCCUGGAAGGUGACGACUUCAAGACGGCCAGCGGGCUGGUGGAGGCCACGGGGGCCGGCUUUGCCAACACCUGGAAGGCACAGUCAAGCUGCCAUGACAAGCUGGACUGGUUGGACGAUCCCUGCUCCCUGAACAUCGAGAGCGCCAACUACGCCGAGCACUGGUGCUCCCUCCUGAAGAAGACAGAGACCCCCUUUGGCAGGUGCCACUCGGCUGUGGACCCUGCUGAGUAUUACAAGAGGUGCAAAUAUGACACGUGUAACUGUCAGAACAAUGAGGACUGCCUGUGCGCCGCCCUGUCCUCCUACGCGCGCGCCUGCACCGCCAAGGGCGUCAUGCUGUGGGGCUGGCGGGAGCAUGUCUGCAACAAGGAUGUGGGCUCCUGCCCCAACUCGCAGGUCUUCCUGUACAACCUGACCACCUGCCAGCAGACCUGCCGCUCCCUCUCCGAGGCCGACAGCCACUGUCUCGAGGGCUUUGCGCCUGUGGACGGCUGCGGCUGCCCUGACCACACCUUCCUGGACGAGAAGGGCCGCUGCGUACCCCUGGCCAAGUGCUCCUGUUACCACCGCGGUCUCUACCUGGAGGCGGGGGAUGUGGUCGUCAGGCAGGAAGAACGAUGUGUGUGCCGGGAUGGGCGGCUGCACUGUAGGCAGAUCCGGCUGAUCGGCCAGAGCUGCACGGCCCCAAAGAUCCACAUGGACUGCAGCAACCUGACUGCACUGGCCACCUCGAAGCCCCGAGCCCUCAGCUGCCAGACGCUGGCCGCCGGCUAUUACCACACAGAGUGUGUCAGUGGCUGUGUGUGCCCCGACGGGCUGAUGGAUGACGGCCGGGGUGGCUGCGUGGUGGAGAAGGAAUGCCCUUGCGUCCAUAACAACGACCUGUAUUCUUCCGGCGCCAAGAUCAAGGUGGACUGCAAUACCUGCACCUGCAAGAGAGGACGCUGGGUGUGCACCCAGGCUGUGUGCCAUGGCACCUGCUCCAUUUACGGGAGUGGCCACUACAUCACCUUUGAUGGGAAGUACUACGACUUUGACGGACACUGCUCCUACGUGGCUGUUCAGGACUACUGCGGCCAGAACUCCUCACUGGGCUCAUUCAGCAUCAUCACCGAGAACGUCCCCUGUGGCACUACGGGCGUCACCUGCUCCAAGGCCAUCAAGAUCUUCAUGGGGAGGACGGAGCUGAAGUUGGAAGACAAGCACCGUGUGGUGAUCCAGCGUGAUGAGGGUCACCACGUGGCCUACACCACGCGGGAGGUGGGCCAGUACCUGGUGGUGGAGUCCAGCACGGGCAUCAUCGUCAUCUGGGACAAGAGGACCACCGUGUUCAUCAAGCUGGCUCCCUCCUACAAGGGCACCGUGUGUGGCCUGUGUGGGAACUUUGACCACCGCUCCAACAACGACUUCACCACGCGGGACCACAUGGUGGUGAGCAGCGAGCUGGACUUCGGGAACAGCUGGAAGGAGGCCCCCACCUGCCCAGAUGUGAGCACCAACCCCGAGCCCUGCAGCCUGAACCCGCACCGCCGCUCCUGGGCCGAGAAGCAGUGCAGCAUCCUCAAAAGCAGCGUGUUCAGCAUCUGCCACAGCAAGGUGGACCCCAAGCCCUUCUACGAGGCCUGUGUGCACGACUCGUGCUCCUGUGACACGGGUGGGGACUGUGAGUGCUUCUGCUCUGCCGUGGCCUCCUACGCCCAGGAGUGUACCAAAGAGGGGGCCUGCGUGUUCUGGAGGACGCCGGACCUGUGCCCCAUAUUCUGCGACUACUACAACCCUCCGCAUGAGUGUGAGUGGCACUAUGAGCCAUGUGGGAACCGGAGCUUCGAGACCUGCAGGACCAUCAACGGCAUCCACUCCAACAUCUCCGUGUCCUACCUGGAGGGCUGCUACCCCCGGUGCCCCAAGGACAGGCCCAUCUAUGAGGAGGAUCUGAAGAAGUGUGUCACUGCAGACAAGUGUGGCUGCUAUGUCGAGGACACCCACUACCCACCUGGAGCAUCGGUUCCCACCGAGGAGACCUGCAAGUCCUGCGUGUGUACCAACUCCUCCCAAGUCGUCUGCAGGCCGGAGGAAGGAAAGAUUCUUAACCAGACCCAGGAUGGCGCCUUCUGCUACUGGGAGAUCUGUGGCCCCAACGGGACGGUGGAGAAGCACUUCAACAUCUGUUCCAUUACGACACGCCCGUCCACCCUGACCACCUUCACCACCAUCACCCUCCCCACCACCCCCACCACCUUCACCACUACCACCACCACCACCACCCCGACCUCCAGCACAGUUUUAUCAACAACUCCGAAGCUGUGCUGCCUCUGGUCUGACUGGAUCAAUGAGGACCACCCCAGCAGUGGCAGCGACGACGGUGACCGAGAAACAUUUGAUGGGGUCUGCGGGGCCCCUGAGGACAUCGAGUGCAGGUCGGUCAAGGAUCCCCACCUCAGCUUGGAGCAGCUAGGCCAGAAGGUGCAGUGUGAUGUCUCUGUUGGGUUCAUUUGCAAGAAUGAAGACCAGUUUGGAAAUGGACCAUUUGGACUGUGUUACGACUACAAGAUACGUGUCAAUUGUUGCUGGCCCAUGGAUAAGUGUAUCACCACUCCCAGCCCUCCAACUACCACUCCCAGCCCUCCACCAACCAGCACGACCACCCUUCCACCAACCACCACCCCCAGCCCUCCAACCACCACCACAACCACCCCUCCACCAACCACCACCCCCAGCCCUCCAAUAACCACCACGACCACCCCUCCACCAACCACCACUCCCAGCCCUCCAAUAAGCACCACAACCACCCCUCCACCAACCACCACUCCCAGCCCUCCAACCACCACUCCCAGCCCUCCAACCACCACUCCCAGCCCUCCAACAACCACCACAACCACCCCUCCACCAACCACCACUCCCAGCCCUCCAACGACUACGCCCAUCACUCCACCAGCCAGCACUACCACCCUUCCACCAACCACCACUCCCAGCCCUCCAACAACCACCACAACCACCCCUCCACCAACCACCACUCCCAUCACCACCACCACCACGGUGACCCCAACCCCAACACCCACCGGCACACAGACCCCAACAACGACACCCAUCACCACCACCACCACGGUGACCCCAACCCCAACACCCACCGGCACACAGACCCCAACAUCGACACCCAUCACCACCACCACUACGGUGACCCCAACCCCAACACCCACCGGCACACAGACCCCAACCACGACACCCAUCACCACCACCACUACGGUGACCCCAACCCCAACACCCACUGGCACACAGACCCCAACCCCAACAGCCAUCACCACCACCACUACGGUGACCCCAACCCCAACACCCACCGGCACACAGACCCCAACCACGACACCCAUCACCACCACCACUACGGUGACACCAACCCCAACACCCACCGGCACACAGUCCCCAACCCCAACAGCCAUCACCACCACCACUACGGUGACCCCAACCCCAACACCCACCGGCACACAGACCCCAACAUCGACACCCAUCACCACCACCACUACGGUGACCCCAACCCCAACACCCACCGGCACACAGACCCCAACCCCGACACCCAUCUCCACCACCACUACGGUGACCCCAACCCCAACACCCACCGGCACACAGACCCCAACCACGACACCCAUCACCACCACCACCACGGUGACCCCAACCCCGACACCCACCGGCACACAGACCCCAACCACGGUACUCAUCACCACCACCACUACGAUGACCCCAACCCCAACACCCACCAGCACAAAGAGUACAACCGUGACACCCAUCACCACCACAACUACGGUGACCGCAACCCCAACACCCACCGGCACACAGACCCCAACCAUGAUACCCAUCAGCACCACCACUACGGUGACCCCAACCCCAACACCCACCACUGGAAGCACGGGGCCCCCCACCCACACAAGCACAGCACCCAUUGCUGAGUUGACCACAUCCAAUCCUCCGCCUGAGUCCUCAACCCCUCAGACCUCUCGGUCCACCUCUUCCCCUCUCACGGAGUCAACCACCCUUCUGAGUACCCUACCACCUGCCAUUGAGAUGACCAGCACGGCCCCACCCUCCACACCCACGGCACCCACGACCACGAGCGGAGGCCACACACUGUCUCCACCGCCCAGCACCACCACGUCCCCUCCAGGCACCCCCACUCGCGGUACCACGACCGGGUCAUCUUCAGCCCCCACCCCCAGCACUGUGCAGACGACCACCACCAGUGCCUGGACCCCAACGCCGACCCCACUCUCCACACCCAGCAUCAUCAGGACCACAGGCCUGAGGCCCUACCCUUCCUCUGUGCUUAUCUGCUGUGUCCUGAACGACACCUACUACGCACCAGGUGAGGAGGUGUACAACGGCACAUACGGAGACACCUGUUAUUUCGUCAACUGCUCACUGAGCUGUACGUUGGAGUUCUAUAACUGGUCCUGCCCAUCCACGCCCUCCCCAACACCCACGCCCUCCAAGUCGACGCCCACGCCUUCCAAGCCAUCGUCCACGCCCUCCAAGCCGACGCCCGGCACCAAGCCCCCCGAGUGCCCAGACUUUGAUCCUCCCAGACAGGAGAACGAGACUUGGUGGCUGUGCGACUGCUUCAUGGCCACGUGCAAGUACAACAACACGGUGGAGAUCGUGAAGGUGGAGUGUGAGCCGCCGCCCAUGCCCACCUGCUCCAACGGCCUCCAACCCGUGCGCGUCGAGGACCCCGACGGCUGCUGCUGGCACUGGGAGUGCGACUGCUACUGCACGGGCUGGGGCGACCCGCACUAUGUCACCUUCGACGGACUCUACUACAGCUACCAGGGCAACUGCACCUACGUGCUGGUGGAGGAGAUCAGCCCCUCCGUGGACAACUUCGGAGUUUACAUCGACAACUACCACUGCGAUCCCAACGACAAGGUGUCCUGUCCCCGCACCCUCAUCGUGCGCCACGAGACCCAGGAGGUGCUGAUCAAGACCGUGCAUAUGAUGCCCAUGCAGGUGCAGGUGCAGGUGAACAGGCAGGCGGUGGCACUGCCCUACAAGAAGUACGGGCUGGAGGUGUACCAGUCUGGCAUCAACUACGUGGUGGACAUCCCCGAGCUGGGUGUCCUCGUCUCCUACAAUGGCCUGUCCUUCUCCGUCAGGCUGCCCUACCACCGGUUUGGCAACAACACCAAGGGCCAGUGUGGCACCUGCACCAACACCACCUCCGACGACUGCAUUCUGCCCAGCGGGGAGAUCGUCUCCAACUGUGAGGCUGCGGCUGACCAGUGGCUGGUGAACGACCCCUCCAAGCCACACUGCCCCCACAGCAGCUCCACGACCAAGCGCCCGGCCGUCACUGUGCCCGGGGGCGGUAAAACGACCCCACACAAGGACUGCACCCCAUCUCCCCUCUGCCAGCUCAUCAAGGACAGCCUGUUUGCCCAGUGCCACGCACUGGUGCCCCCGCAGCACUACUACGAUGCCUGCGUGUUCGACAGCUGCUUCAUGCCGGGCUCGAGCCUGGAGUGCGCCAGUCUGCAGGCCUACGCAGCCCUCUGUGCCCAGCAGAACAUCUGCCUCGACUGGCGGAACCACACGCAUGGGGCCUGCUUGGUGGAGUGCCCAUCUCACAGGGAGUACCAGGCCUGUGGCCCUGCAGAAGAGCCCACGUGCAAAUCCAGCUCCUCCCAGCAGAACAACACAGUCCUGGUGGAAGGCUGCUUCUGUCCUGAGGGCACCAUGAACUACGCUCCUGGCUUUGAUGUCUGCGUGAAGACCUGCGGCUGUGUGGGACCUGACAAUGUGCCCAGAGAGUUUGGGGAGCACUUCGAGUUCGACUGCAAGAACUGUGUCUGCCUGGAGGGUGGAAGUGGCAUCAUCUGCCAACCCAAGAGGUGCAGCCAGAAGCCCGUUACCCACUGCGUGGAAGACGGCACCUACCUCGCCACGGAGGUCAACCCUGCCGACACCUGCUGCAACAUUACCGUCUGCAAGUGCAACACCAGCCUGUGCAAAGAGAAGCCCUCCGUGUGCCCGCUGGGAUUCGAAGUGAAGAGCAAGAUGGUGCCUGGAAGGUGCUGUCCUUUCUACUGGUGUGAGUCCAAGGGGGUGUGUGUUCACGGGAAUGCUGAGUACCAGCCCGGUUCUCCAGUUUAUUCCUCCAAGUGCCAGGACUGCGUGUGCACGGACAAGGUGGACAACAACACCCUGCUCAACGUCAUCGCCUGCACCCACGUGCCCUGCAACACCUCCUGCAGCCCUGGCUUCGAACUCAUGGAGGCCCCCGGGGAGUGCUGUAAGAAGUGUGAACAGACGCACUGUAUCAUCAAACGGCCCGACAACCAGCACGUCAUCCUGAAGCCCGGGGACUUCAAGAGCGACCCGAAGAACAACUGCACAUUCUUCAGCUGCGUGAAGAUCCACAACCAGCUCAUCUCGUCCGUCUCCAACAUCACCUGCCCCAACUUUGAUGCCAGCAUUUGCAUCCCGGGCUCCAUCACAUUCAUGCCCAAUGGAUGCUGCAAGACCUGCACCCCUCGCAAUGAGACCAGGGUGCCCUGCUCCACCGUCCCCGUCACCACGGAGGUUUCGUACGCCGGCUGCACCAAGACCGUCCUCAUGAAUCAUUGCUCCGGGUCCUGCGGGACAUUUGUCAUGUACUCGGCCAAGGCCCAGGCCCUGGACCACAGCUGCUCCUGCUGCAAAGAGGAGAAAACCAGCCAGCGUGAGGUGGUCCUGAGCUGCCCCAAUGGCGGCUCGCUGACACACACCUACACCCACAUCGAGAGCUGCCAGUGCCAGGACACCGUCUGCGGGCUCCCCACCGGCACCUCCCGCCGGGCCCGGCGCUCCCCUAGGCAUCUGGGGAGCGGGUGAGCGGGGUGGGCACAGCCCCCUUCACUGCCCUCGACAGCUUUACCUCCCCCGGACCCUCUGAGCCUCCUAAGCUCGGCUUCCUCUCUUCAGAUAUUUAUUGUCUGAGUCUUUGUUCAGUCCUUGCUUUCCAAUAAUAAACUCAGGGGGACAUGC